GCUCCUCAGUCCCUGCCCUGGCGCGCCCGCUCCCGGCCCCGCGUGCGGCGCUGGGAAAGGGGUGUCGGGUUACCAGCGCGGGGGCUACAGUUAGCCUCGAGAACCUUUGCUUUCAGCCGGACUCCGGACUCCUCCGGGGACAGCGCAGCGCCCGCCAGAGCCCUCGGCGCUCCCUCCCGCUGGCGGCUUCCGCAGCCUUCAAGGAUGGCGCUGGCGGCUUUGAUGAUCGCCCUCGGCAGCCUCGGCCUCCACACCUGGCAGGCCCAGGCUGUUCCCAUCCUGCCCCUGGGCCUGGCUCCAGACACCUUUGACGAUACCUAUGUGGGUUGUGCAGAGGAGAUGGAGGAGAAGGCAGCCCCCCUGCUAAAGGAGGAAAUGGCCCACCAUGCCCUGCUGCGGGAAUCCUGGGAGGCAGCCCAGGAGACCUGGGAGGACAAGCGUCGAGGGCUUACCUUGCCCCCUGGCUUCAAAGCCCAGAAUGGAAUAGCCAUUAUGGUCUACACCAACUCAUCGAACACCUUGUACUGGGAGUUGAAUCAGGCCGUGCGGACGGGCGGAGGCUCCCGGGAGCUCUACAUGAGGCACUUUCCCUUCAAGGCCCUGCAUUUCUACCUGAUCCGGGCCCUGCAGCUGCUGCGAGGCAGUGGGGGCUGCAGCAGGGGACCUGGGGAGGUGGUGUUCCGAGGUGUGGGCAGCCUUCGCUUUGAACCCAAGAGGCUGGGAGACUCUGUCCGCUUGGGCCAGUUUGCCUCCAGCUCCCUGGAUAAGGCAGUGGCCCACAGAUUUGGUAAUGCCACCCUCUUCUCUCUAACAACUUGCUUUGGGGCCCCUAUACAGGCCUUCUCUGUCUUUCCCAAGGAGCGCGAGGUGCUGAUUCCCCCCCAUGAAGUCUUUUUGGUUACCAGAUUCUCUCAGGAUGGAGCCCAGAGCUUGGUGACUCUCUGGAGCUAUAAUCAGACCUGUAGCCAUUUUAACUGCGCCUAUCUGGGUGGGGAGAAGAGGCGGGGCUGUGUGUCUGCGCCAGCAGGGGUGCAGCUAGGGUCACAAUCUGAGGGGGCCUCCUCUCUGCCCCCCUGGAAGACUCUGCUCUUGGCCCCUGGAGAGUUCCAGCUCUCAGGGGUUGGGCCCUGAAAGUCCAACAUCUGCCACUUAGGAGCCCUGGGAACGGGUGACCUUCAUAUGACGAAGAGGCACCUCCAGCAGCCUUGAGAAGCAAGAACAUGGUUCCGGACCCAGCCCUAGCAGCCUUCUCCCCAACCAGGAUGUUGGCCUGGGGAGGCCACAGCAGGGCUGAGGGAACUCUGCUAUGUGAUGGGGACUUCCUGGGACAAGCAAGGAAAGUACUGAGGCAGCCACUUGAUUGAACGGUGUUGCAAUGUGGAGACAUGGAGUUUUAUUGAGGUAGCUACGUGAUUAAAUGGUAUUGCAGUGUGGA